AGACCUAGAAAAGAAUCGUGACGGGCAGGAAACCAUUACACCACCACCUGGGCUGUGCUCUCCGGCUCCCGCCGCCACCCCCGCCCUCGCCUUCGCCUCCGCCUCCGGUGAGUUCAGGGCGGUUGCCUUUAGGGUGUGUCCCUAAUUGACGGGGUCGGGGACGGAGAGAAGGGUAACACCAGGCUGGGUCGGAGACCGGCGGAGGCGAGGAAAUCCUAAGAGCGUGACCGUUGAUGAUGCAGGGAACCGUCGGGUGUGACCAUUGAGAGGGAAAAGGUUGGAGAAAGGGUCUCUACCAUGAUGCCUGUGGUGCGGUGAGGGAAUCCUCGGGUGUGGCAGCAGGUGCACAUUAAAGAUCCAAAGUCAUGACUGACUCCAAGUAUUUCACAACCAAUAAAAAAGGAGAAAUAUUUGAACUAAAAGCUGAACUCAACAAUGAAAAGAAAGAAAAGAGAAAGGAGGCUGUGAAGAAAGUGAUUGCUGCUAUGACCGUGGGGAAGGAUGUUAGUUCUCUCUUUCCAGACGUAGUGAACUGUAUGCAGACUGACAAUCUGGAACUAAAGAAGCUUGUGUAUCUCUACUUGAUGAACUACGCCAAGAGUCAGCCAGACAUGGCCAUCAUGGCUGUAAACAGCUUUGUGAAGGACUGUGAAGAUCCUAAUCCUUUGAUUCGAGCCUUGGCAGUCAGAACCAUGGGGUGCAUCCGGGUAGACAAAAUUACAGAAUAUCUCUGUGAGCCGCUCCGCAAGUGCUUGAAGGAUGAGGAUCCCUAUGUUCGGAAAACAGCAGCAGUCUGCGUGGCAAAACUCCAUGAUAUCAAUGCCCAAAUGGUGGAAGAUCAGGGAUUUCUGGAUUCUCUACGGGAUCUCAUAGCAGAUUCAAAUCCAAUGGUGGUGGCUAAUGCCGUAGCGGCAUUAUCUGAAAUCAGUGAGUCUCACCCAAACAGCAACUUACUUGAUCUGAACCCACAGAACAUUAAUAAGCUGCUGACAGCCCUGAAUGAAUGCACUGAAUGGGGCCAGAUUUUCAUCCUGGACUGCCUGUCUAAUUACAACCCUAAAGAUGAUCGGGAGGCUCAGAGCAUCUGUGAGCGGGUAACUCCCCGGCUAUCCCAUGCCAACUCAGCAGUGGUGCUUUCAGCGGUAAAAGUCCUAAUGAAGUUUCUAGAAUUGUUACCUAAGGAUUCUGACUACUACAAUAUGCUGCUGAAGAAGUUAGCCCCUCCACUUGUCACUUUGCUGUCUGGGGAGCCAGAAGUGCAGUAUGUCGCCCUGAGGAACAUCAACUUAAUUGUCCAGAAAAGGCCUGAAAUCUUGAAGCAGGAAAUCAAAGUCUUCUUUGUGAAGUACAAUGAUCCCAUCUAUGUUAAACUAGAGAAGUUGGACAUCAUGAUUCGUUUGGCAUCUCAAGCCAACAUUGCUCAGGUUCUGGCAGAACUGAAAGAAUAUGCUACAGAGGUGGAUGUUGACUUUGUUCGAAAAGCUGUGCGGGCCAUUGGACGGUGUGCCAUCAAGGUGGAGCAAUCUGCAGAGCGCUGUGUAAGCACAUUGCUUGAUCUAAUCCAGACCAAAGUGAAUUAUGUGGUCCAAGAAGCAAUUGUUGUCAUCAGGGACAUCUUCCGCAAAUACCCCAACAAGUAUGAAAGUAUCAUCGCCACUCUGUGUGAGAACUUAGACUCGCUGGAUGAGCCAGAUGCUCGAGCAGCUAUGAUUUGGAUUGUGGGAGAAUAUGCUGAAAGAAUUGACAAUGCAGAUGAGUUACUAGAAAGCUUCCUGGAGGGUUUUCACGAUGAAAGCACCCAGGUGCAGCUCACUCUGCUUACUGCCAUAGUGAAGCUGUUUCUCAAGAAACCAUCAGAAACACAGGAGCUAGUCCAGCAGGUCUUGAGUUUGGCAACACAGGAUUCUGAUAAUCCUGACCUUCGAGACCGGGGCUAUAUUUAUUGGCGCCUUCUCUCAACUGACCCUGUUACAGCUAAAGAAGUAGUCUUGUCUGAGAAGCCACUGAUCUCUGAGGAGACGGACCUUAUUGAGCCAACUCUGCUGGAUGAGCUAAUCUGCCACAUUGGUUCUUUGGCCUCUGUGUAUCAUAAGCCUCCCAAUGCUUUUGUGGAAGGAAGUCAUGGAAUUCAUCGUAAACACUUGCCAAUUCAUCAUGGGAGCACUGAUGCAGGUGACAGCCCUGUUGGCACUACCACUGCAACGAACCUGGAACAGCCUCAGGUUAUCCCCUCUCAAGGUGAUCUUCUAGGGGAUCUUUUAAACCUUGACCUCGGUCCCCCAGUCAAUGUGCCACAGGUGUCCUCCAUGCAGAUGGGAGCAGUGGAUCUCCUAGGAGGAGGACUAGAUAGUCUGCUUGGCAGUGACCUUGGCGGGGGCAUUGGAGGAAGUCCGGCAGUGGGACAAUCCUUCAUCCCAUCAUCGGUGCCUGCAACCUUUGCUCCUUCACCUACACCUGCUGUGGUCAGCAGUGGACUGAAUGACCUGUUUGAACUCUCCACAGGGAUAGGCAUGGCACCUGGUGGAUAUGUGGCUCCUAAGGCUGUCUGGCUACCUGCAGUAAAGGCUAAAGGCUUGGAGAUUUCCGGAACAUUUACUCACCGCCAAGGGCACAUCUAUAUGGAAAUGAACUUCACCAAUAAAGCUCUGCAGCACAUGACAGAUUUUGCAAUCCAGUUUAACAAAAAUAGCUUUGGUGUCAUCCCCAGCACUCCUCUGGCCAUCCAUACACCACUGAUGCCAAACCAGAGCAUUGAUGUCUCCCUGCCUCUCAAUACCUUGGGCCCAGUCAUGAAGAUGGAACCUCUGAAUAACCUCCAGGUUAAAAGCAAGGAGAAUAAUUGGAUGGACACUUCUGGGAGAGAGAACGCAAAUAUUAUGGAGAAGGGAAUACAGGCACCAUUUAAAGUAAGGAAGGUGGCUGUGAAAAACAAUAUCGAUGUCUUCUACUUCAGCUGCCUCAUCCCACUCAAUGUGCUUUUUGUAGAAGAUGGCAAAAUGGAGCGCCAGGUCUUCCUUGCAACAUGGAAGGAUAUUCCCAAUGAAAAUGAACUUCAGUUUCAGAUUAAGGAAUGUCAUUUAAAUGCUGACACUGUUUCCAGCAAGUUGCAAAACAACAAUGUUUAUACUAUUGCCAAGAGGAAUGUGGAAGGGCAGGACAUGCUGUACCAAUCCCUGAAGCUCACUAAUGGCAUUUGGAUUUUGGCCGAACUACGUAUCCAGCCAGGAAACCCCAAUUACACGCUGUCACUGAAGUGUAGAGCUCCUGAAGUCUCUCAAUACAUCUAUCAGGUCUACGACAGCAUUUUGAAAAACUAACAAGACUGGUCCAGUACCCUUCAACCAUGCUGUGAUCGGUGCAAGUCAAGAACUCUUAACUGGAAGAAAUUGUAUUGCUGCGUAGAAUCUGAACACACUGAGGCCACCUAGCAAGGUAGUAACUAGUCUAACCUGUGCUAACAUUAGGGCACAACCUGUUGGAUAGUUUUAGCUUCCUGUGAACAUUUGUAACCACUGCUUCAGUCACCUCCCACCUCUUGCCACCUGCUGCUGCUAUCUGUCCUUACUUGUGGGCUUCUCCAUGCUGUGCCAAUGGCUGGCUUUUUCUACACCCUCUUUUGAGUGUAGUUUGGUAUUUUGUAAUUGAGAGCUCAUUUCAAAAGCAGAAAAAGACAACAAAUAUUAAAGCAAGGAAAAGUGUAACUGAAACACUGCACUUUACUGUUUUAUACUUUUGUACAUAUGAGAAAUCAAGGGAUUAGUGCAACCAGUAGAAAGCAUUGAAAUGACUGUCAUUAACCACACAGUCCUGGAGGCAGAGAUGCAGUUACCUACCCUAGCUUUUGAUGGGUUCUCUUACCUGUAGUAGCCUUAUCCCUGGUCAUUUGGAUUUUCAGUUUGCUUUUUUCUUUUUUUCCCCUCCAAACUCCUUUUCCUUGGCCAAGCCUUCAUGCUUCCCCCUUUCCAUAUUAUAAUCUCAUUUGAUUGCUCUGCAGUUGGGAACGGUGAUCUUCUUGAAUGAUGUUUCAGUGUGCAAAAACUAUAGAGCCUGUCAGCACCAAAGCUGACAGAAGUUAUACCUUACUCCUUUCCUUUCCCCUGAACAAACCUGCUAAUCCCACUAAUUCAGGAAUUUGAGUAGAGAUGGGGAACAAGAACCCAGAUGCUGUCCCCUCACCCCCUCUCCUGUAUUUCUCAGGUCCAGUUCAAAUCUAAAAUUCUACUUUUAGAGUUGAAACAGAGUAAUAACUUAUCUAACCCUCUUUUCCUACAAAGGAGAAAGAUAAAAGGCACAAAGGUUACCGCCAAGGCCCGUCAGCUGUGUAGUGGCAAAGCCGAGACCGAGUCUCCUAAGUCCCCGUCAGUGUGGUUUUCACCACAGGACUGUCUCUUGUCGUUUUCCCCUAAUGCCUUCUCCUGCCUUUUCUGUGCCUAGUUUUUGGCUCUUCACAUAUUCCAUAUUGAUUUUGACGCUCUGUAUAUUGGCAUCAGGUGGCAGCUGAAUAUCUUUUGAAUUACUCGAAGGUAAAGCCAGAUGCCAGAAUGAAGGUGUAGCCAGUGUUUCCCAUAUGCCCCUGGAGCCCCACUUAUUGAGGCCAGCAGAAUAGGUGCAGAGAUGAAGUGAGCUUAGAGAUGUUGCAAAUGCUCUUUAUCCCUUCAGCUCUCUGAUCUGCUCUUUCUUCAUGAUACUUAGUCUGCAGGGCAUAUUAAGAUCAUCCCAGAGGUUCAGGCAGUUCCUGUCAUCUCUGAAAAGACUGGGGGAUAUGAAAUCUUCCCCCUACCCCACUUAAUGCGUUGGAUAUGAUUUUUCAAAGAAUGCUUCAUGCCCAAAAUACCAGCCUGUUUAGCAGUGUUACACUGUUUGAUCUGCGGGCACUUGUUGCAUUGCCUGGCACCCAAUAUUCAGGGUCCAUGACUAAGACUGGUCUUCUCAGAUGCCCUGCUUAAAUCAGGGGCACUUCAGGCUCCACAGGCGUCAUGUUGGACUGAGACCUAACUCACUGGACUCAGAGGAGGAAUCGUGGAAAACAAGAGCAAAACUACCCCACACCCCUAUUUCAUGUCUGAAAUAACCCUGUUUCAUACCAGUUGCAAAGCUUGUGGGGAGCGGUCCCACAAAGCACUUUCUUAAACCUUGAGAAUCUCCAAGAGAAAAAUAUUUGGGGAAGGAGGGAGGAAAUAUGUCCCUUGCACACCACCCCUGAAGCACAUGGCAGUAGGAAACAGCAUAGGAUUGUAUGUGGGAGGUGGAUAGGUCGGUGAUGUGUGGAGCGGAAAAGCAGGUUGGUAAAGUUCCCUUCUUGGGACUUAUUCCUGGAGUCAGUGGAUACAAGUAGUGCAGAAGGUUCACACUGCAAAUAGUGUUCUCAUCUCAAAGCAAACUAUCAUUCCAGAAGGAAAAGUGUGUCAGGGCAAGCAGACAACACAAUUUCCUAUCAGAAUAUGUCCCUCAACCCCCGAAACAAGGCUUCUCUCAGCCUCCCCACCAGUGAUGGAUAACAGCUCCUAUUCUCAGCUGACCUGACUGAGCCAACCCAUGAACUCUUCACUCCUUGGGGAAGCCACCUCCCAUCACACCCCUGAGCAGAGUUAGGGAGGAAUUCUACUUCCCAUAAAAGGACCUCUCCUGAGAGGCAAAACCUGUUGCCUCCACCACGGCUUCCCUCUUGGCUCAUUCCAAGCUUGGCCAAAUUGGGGAAGUGGGAUGGAGGUUGCCCUGCAUCCCCCCUCCUCUGCCUGAGUGUGUCUUUGUAAUGUCAGCUGGCAUCAUACAAAGAGCAGGAGAAGCAAACACCCAGAACUCUUUUGCUGGUCAGAGAUUCCCUGAGUGUCUGUCCUCACCCAAGCCUGCUCUGUGUCUGUGUUGUGAAGCUUGAGACUCUGGAAAGAAAUGGGGAGGGGGGGCAGGGGAAAUGUUGCCCUAAGAAUGCUUCUCAUUCCUCUGUUCUUAUUGGGUCCUGUUUUUCGGGAGGGUGGGGGUUGGGGGAAGCUUGACCUUGUGUCUUCGUCAAUAAACUCACAUUUACACAAAA